AUAACGGCUUGGCUUACCUGUAACGGGUACGCUUCGCUUUGCGUUCCUCGCUUGGCCUUGCGUUCCUAGCUUGGCUUGGCGUUAGUCGCUUUGCCUGGUGUUUCUUGCUUGGAUUGGCGUUUCCUCCCUCGCAUUCCUUUGCUGGGCUUGACUUUUUCUCUGCUGGGUUUGGCAUUCCCUUGACUGGGCUGGGUGUUUCCUUGGGAGGGGGGGCUUGGCCUUUCCUGGGGUGGGCGUUGGGUCCCCCUGGUGGGCGUGGGCUUUCCCCGGGUGGGUGUGGGUUUUCCCUGGGUGGGGUGGACUGGGCUCCCUUGCUGGGGUUGGCAAGUUUUGGCUGGGAUUGACCUUUCUCUUCAAACAGAUUGGAAACCCAGGGUUUCCUGCUAGUUGGUGAAACUGGUUGGUAGACGCGAUCUGUUCGCUACUACCGGCCUCCCCGGGCUGUUAAAAGCAGAUGGUGACUGAGGUUUGUUCAAUGCCCGCUGCCUCUGCUGUGAAGAAGCCAUUCGAUCUCAGGAGCAAGAUGGGCAAGUGGUUUCACCACCGCUUCCCCUGCUGCAAGGGGAGCGGCAAGAGCAACAUGGGCACUUCUGGAGACCACGACGACUCCUUUAUGAAGAUGCUCAGGAGCAAGAUGGGCAAGUGUUGCCACCACUGCUUCCCCUGCUGCAGGGGGAGCGGCACGAGCAACGUGGGCACUUCUGGAGACCAUGACAACUCCUUUAUGAAGACGCUCAGGAGCAAGAUGGGCAAGUGGUGCUGUCACUGCUUCCCCUGCUGCAGGGGGAGCGGCAAGAGCAACGUGGGCGCUUGGGGAGACUACGACGACAGCGCCUUCAUGGAGCCGAGGUACCACGUCCGUCGAGAAGAUCUGGACAAGCUCCACAGAGCUGCCUGGUGGGGUAAGGUCCCCAGAAAGGAUCUCAUCGUCAUGCUCAGGGACACGGACAUGAACAAGAGGGACAAGCAAAAGAGGACUGCUCUACAUUUGGCCUCUGCCAAUGGAAAUUCAGAAGUAGUACAACUCCUGCUGGACAGACGAUGUCAACUUAAUGUCCUUGACAACAAAAAAAGGACAGCUCUGAUAAAGGCCGUACAAUGCCAGGAAGAUGAAUGUGUGUUAAUGUUGCUGGAACAUGGCGCUGAUCAAAAUAUUCCAGAUGAGUAUGGAAAUACCACUCUACACUAUGCUGUCCACAAUGAAGAUAAAUUAAUGGCCAAAGCACUGCUCUUAUAUGGUGCUGAUAUUGAAUCAAAAAACAAGUGUGGCCUCACACCACUUUUGCUUGGCGUACAUGAACAAAAACAGCAAGUGGUGAAAUUUUUAAUCAAGAAAAAAGCUAAUUUAAAUGCACUUGAUAGAUAUGGAAGAACUGCCCUCAUACUUGCUGUAUGUUGUGGAUCAGCAAGUAUAGUCAAUCUUCUCCUUGAGCAAAAUGUUGAUGUAUCUUCUCAAGAUCUAUCUGGACAGACGGCCAGAGAGUAUGCUGUUUCUAGUCAUCAUCAUGUAAUUUGUGAAUUACUUUCUGACUAUAAAGAAAAACAGAUGCUAAAAAUCUCUUCUGAAAACAGCAAUCCAGAACAAGACUUAAAGCUAACAUCAGAGGAAGAGUCACAAAGGCUUAAAGUCAGUGAAAAUAGCCAGCCAGAGAAAAUGUCUCAAGAACCAGAAAUAAAUAAGGACUGUGAUAGAGAGGUUGAAGAAGAAAUAAAGAAGCAUGGAAGUAAUCCUGUGGGAUUACCAGAAAACCUGACUAAUGGUGCCAGUGCUGGCAAUGGUGAUGAUGGAUUAAUUCCACAAAGGAGGAGCAGAAAACCUGAAAAUCAGCAAUUUCCUGACACUGAGAAUGAAGAGUAUCACAGUGACGAACAAAAUGAUACCCGGAAACAACUUUCUGAAGAACAGAACACUGGAAUAUCACAAGAUGAGAUUCUGACUAAUAAACAAAAGCAGAUAGAAGUGGCUGAAAAGAAAAUGAAUUCUGAGCUUUCUCUUAGUCAUAAGAAAGAAGAAGAUCUCUUGCGUGAAAACAGCAUGUUGCAGGAAGAAAUUGCCAUGCUAAUUUCUGGAGACUGGAACUAGAUGAAACAAAACAUCAGAACCAGCUAAGGGAAAAUAAAAUUUUGGAGGAAAUUGAAAGUGUGAAAGAAAAGACUGAUAAACUUCUAAGGGCUAUGCAAUUGAAUGAAGAAGCAUUAACGAAAACCAAUAUUUAAGUACAGUGGACAGCUUAGGAUUUUGACAACUGAGAAUGCUCAGUUCUGAACUGGAGAAUGUAAGACACAGCUAGGAAACACUGGAAAUGGAAAUUCAAUCAUGUCAUUGUAGACUGACUACUGCUCUACAUGAUUGUGAUCAAAGUCAGAUAGCUGAAAGGGACUUCUUUCCAGAGAACAAACAUGAACAGGUUUAUUUACAGGAGAAAAUGAAUUCUCAUAUAUCUCACCUAAAAGAUAACAGUGAGAUUCUUUCUGAACAACUCUAACGCUGACAGUAAAAUUAACAACCUAAAAAUUAAGCUCCAUCACACAGGAUAAAUUCUGAGAGAAAAGAUGAGGCAGGCCACCAUCUUUCCUGUUUGGGCAACUUAGCGAUUCCAGCGUGCGGGCUUUGGAGAGUACAAACCCACCAGGGGCAGAAGAGAUCCUGUGGCAUAGCACAGCUGCUUUACCAAAUCAUGUCCAGAAUGCUUCUGUAAGCAGGCCUCUGAUCCUGUUCCUCGUCACUGGACAGGAUCUCCCACCUGAGGCCUCCAGCUACACCCACCAGUGUUCCCUGGCCAAUGGAGAUUUGAAACCUUCCUGGGACAGAGUUCCCAGAGAGAGGGGUGGGCCAUGACCUUUGUUGUUUGGGCAACUAGCCCUUCUGGCCUGUGGGCUUUGGAGAGCCCAAGCUGACCAGGGGUGGAAGUGGUACCUCAGCACAGAACAGCCACCCUGCGAAAACGUGGCCAGAUUCUUGUUUAAGCCAGUCCCCAACCACAUUUCUAAUCACUGGGUGGAGCCUUUCAACCAGGGUCUCCAGCCACCUUCACUGCUGUUCUCUGGCUCACAGAGGUUUCAGGCCUCCUGAGUCAGAGCUCCCAGGGGGAGGACCAGACUGUCAUCUUUGCUGUUUGGAUGACUCAGCCAGUUCAGUCUUAGAGUUUCAGAGUGUCUGAGGAGACCAGGGGCUGAAGUGAACCCCCCACACAGCAUAGCCACUCUACAAAAACGUGGCCAGACUUCUUUUUUAAACAAGUCCCUAUUCCUGUUCCUCCUUACUAGGCAAGACUUCUCAACUUGCUUCCAGUCACAUCCUACAGGUGUGUUGAGAUUGGCAACAGGUUCAUACCUCAGAGGUACAGAGCUCCCAGAGGGAAGGGCAGGCUAUCGUCUUUGCUUUUUCUCAGGCUUCACUGCUGAUACCUUCAGCCACUGGAAAAUACGAGGCAAUUGGCGACUGGAGUGGACCCCCAGCAUACCACGGCAGCCCCACAGAAAAGUGGCCAGACUGUUAUGUGGGUGCCCAUUUCCAUAUCUCCUCGAUGGGCAGGUCUUCCUGGCCUGGGUCUCCAGCCAGCCCCCCACUUGAGCUUUCAAGCCAGUAGCAACUCAGCAACUCCCUGGACAGAGCUUCCAGGAGCAACAGAAAUCCUCUCUGCCACUGCCUCUGCAGUGGAACUGCCCUUGCUACCCUCAGAAUAUCAAGGGAGCAAAGACCCUAAGUGCCAUAUUGACACCUCCAACAAGCUGCAGUUGACACAAGGAACAAGUCAGUCCAUCUUCCACAGGUACAACACACCCCUUACUGCUCAUCACCAGACAAGGAACCGUGGCUUGGGCCCACAACACAGACCCUCCAUCCUGGGGUGAUUACAUUAAGUAACUGCUAACUUACACCUCUCUGGGGUGGAGCCCCCAGGAGACAAGGAAAGUAGUGGAGCAGCAAGUCAGCUGAUGUGGAGCCUGGAGGGCAGGGACAGCUAUGUCUCUAGGCUCCACUUGCUCUUAUGAGACACUUUAUCCCAGCACUUUAGGAGUGCUGAGGUCAGACCAGCCCCAUCUCACGUGCAAGAUUGCCCAGCACAGAUCAGGUCUAAGAGUUCUCUUCGUAAAAAAGGGGACUUGCUUAAAAAAGAAGUCUGGCCACGUUUGUGUAGAGCAGUUGUGCUGUGCUGAGGAUUCACUUUUGAGAGAGUUCUCCUCUGAGACCUGAUCUGUGCUGGGCAGUCUUGCACAUGAGAUGGGGCUGGUCUGACCUCAGCACCCCUUAGUCUGCUUGCCUCUCCCAGGACCCCAGCCAGGCCACACCUGCUUAGAGGGCACUUUCGGGUGCCCACACCAUAGCUUCUGUACAAGCGGACCGUGCCUGAUCAGUGGAGAGCUGCAGCAAGGUGACCUCUACAGCCACGCACUAGCCUGCACAUUACCAUUCCAUACUGCAGCCCUUUAUAUGGAAACUUCCUACAUCACUUUGCUGUGUGUGUUUACACAGGUGGGUUUUGUUGUACUUGCCCUAACAGCAUAUGGGAAUGCAGCACACACCCCAACCCACACCAACUGCCACUGAAGAUGAAGCCAUGGUGGGCACAGAACCAAAAACCCCACCCCUGCUAGCAUCUCACCCUUGAGGUAAUGCUGUGCAGAGGAAAAGGGACCUUCUUAUACCCUGAGUGACCACUGUUGCUUGGGGGGGAUCAGAGAAGGCACCUUCACUGGCCAGCCACCCACCCCAAACCAGCACUACCUCCAGUGCAACAGCACACACAGUCAGCAGGGGCCCGUGGCCCACACCCCAGCUGUUUUGCCUCCACCACUGGGUGAAUGCCCACAGGGAGGCAGGGACUUUUGCAUCUGCUAGCAUUCUGCCACAGCUGCUGCACUUUGGUCCCCUCAGUGCAGUGGACUCCAAACCUCGAGGAGCCAGAGGACAAAGUUGUGGCCCAAUACAAGUUCCCCAGAGUUAAAGCACACAGUCCAAGAAUUGGGAGCUGCAUGUUGGCCCCUUAAAAUCCUCCAAAAACAAAACCUGUUGGCUGAAUCCACCUUACACCACAAUCAAAUCCUCAAGGUCAUCAGAUAUAAUAAAGGAAAAAUACCCUGUCCAAAGGUCAGCAACCUCAAAGAUUGAAGAUGGAUAAGCCCAUAAAGAUGAGAAAAAGACUCUGUGCAAGAACACUGAAAACUCAAAAAUUCAGCAUACCUUCUUUUCUCCAAAUGACUGCAUCAACUCUCCAGCAAGUGUUCAGAACUGGGCUGAGGCUGAGAUGUCUGAAAUGAUACAAGCAGAGUUCAGGAUAUGGGUAGGAACAAAGUUCAUUGAGUGAAAGAAGUAUGUUGUAAUCCAAUACAAGGAAGCUAAAAAUCAUUGUAAAACAUUGCAGGAACUAACAGACAAAAUAGUGAGUAUAAAGAAGAAAAUAACUGACCUGACAGAGCUGUAAAUCACACUAGAAGAAUUUUCAUAAUGUAGUCACAUGGUGAUUGUGUGUGAUUGCAUUAUGAAUAUUAUUGUAGUAUGUGUGGGCACCUGAGAGUGCCCUGUAAGCAGGUGUGGCCAGGCUGGGGUCCUGGGAGAGGCAAGCAGACUAGGGAGGGCUGAGGUCAGACCAGCUCCAUCUCAUGUGCAAGACCAUCUAACAGAAUAGACCAAGAAGAGGAAAGAAUCCCAGAGCUUGAAAACUGGCUUUCUGAAAUAAAACAGGCAAACAAGAAUGGGGGAAAAAAGAAUGAAAGGGAAUGAACAAAACAUCCGAGAAAUAUGGGAUUAUAUAAACGACCAAAUCUAUGACUGAUUAAUGUACCUGAAAGAGAUGAGGAGAAUGGAACCAACUUGGAAAACACAUUUCAGAAUAUCAUUCAUGAGAAUGUCCCCAACCUAGCCAGACAGGCCAACAUUCAACUUCAGGAAAUCCAGAGAACCUCAGUAAGAUAUGCCAUGAGAAGAUCAUCCCCAAGACACAUAAUCAUCAGAUUCUCUGAGGUCAAAAUAAAAGAAAAAAUGUUAAAGGCAGCUAGGGAGAAAGGCAACAUCACCUGCAAAGGGAAUUCCAUCAGACUUAGCAGACCUCUCAACUGAAACUGUACAAGCCAGAAAAGACAUUCAACAUUUCAAAGAAAAGAAAUUUCAACCCAGAAUUUCAUGUCCAGCAAAAUUAAGCAUCAUAAGUGAAGGAGAAACAAGAUCGUUUUCAGACAAGCAAAUGCUGAGGGAAUUCGUUAUCACCAGACCUACCUUACAAGAGCUCCUGAAGGAAGCACUAAAUAUGGAAAGAAAAGACCACCACCAGCCACUACAAAAACACACUGAAGUACACAGACAAGUGAUGCUAAAAACCAACCACAUACAUAAGUCUGCAAAAGAGCCAGCUGACAGCAUGAUGACAGGAUCAAAUCCACACAUACCAUUACUAACCUUAAAUGGAAAUGGGCUAAAUGCUCCAAUUGAAAGACACAGGGGGCAAGCUGGAUAAAGAACCAAGACCCAUUGGAGUAUGCCGUCUUCAAGAAACCCAUCUCACAUGCAGUGCCAUACAUAGGCUCAAAAUAAAGGAAUGGAGAAAAAUAUUUCAAGGAAAUGGAAAACAGAAAAAAGCAGGUGUUGCACUCCUAGUUUCUGACAAAACAGACUAUACCAAUAAAGAUUUAAAAAAAAAAAAA